GUGCAAUGGCGUGAUCUCAGCACAUCACAACCUCCACCUCCUGGGUUCAAGCGAUUCUCCUGCCUCAGCCUCCUGAGUAGCUGGGAUUACAGGCAUGCACCACCAUGCCUGGCUAAUUUUGUAUUUUUAGUAGAGACGGGGUUUCUUCAUGUUGAUCAGGCUGGUCUCGAACUCCCGACCUCAGGUGAUCUGCCUGCCUCAUUACGAGCAGCAAAAAUUCAUAAUCCUGUGACAAUACCCAAUAUCACUAAUAAUACAGCUUGUGAUGACUGA